UAGUUUUUUGUUGCAAUGGGGUUUUGCUAUGUUGCCCAGGCUGGUGUCAAACUCCUGGGCUCAAGUGAUCCUCUCCCUACCUGGGCCUGCCAAUGUGCUGGGAUUUCAAGUGUGAGCCACCACACCCCGCCUUUCCCCAAUUUUAAAUCCAACAUGGCAGUUCUGGAUUAAGGGAGUCACUCUUCCUAUAUGUCUUCCCAGUCUGGAUUUUGAAGCAGCUGCCUUUUUGCUUCCUAAUGAUGCUAGCCUAUCCAAACUAGAAAUAAUCUUAUAUAAUCAUUGAUGCCUUGACUCAUUUGUAUGUAUCUGUAUUUUUAAACUUUUUAUCUUUCAUUACCAAAUGACUGCUUUCUGAUACCCAGGCCUAGGCUUAAACACUGGCAUAUAUGGAGAGAACAGUUGCCACUCGACUCAGAGAUUGAGUAGACACCCAAAGAACUGCAGUUCUUAAGCCUUAGGAGAAGCGAGAGAAAUGGGCCAGGUGCGGUGGCUCAUGCCUGUAAUCCCAGCACUUUGGGAGGCUGAGAUGGGCAGAUCACCUGAGGCCAGGAGUUCGAGACCAGCCUGGCCAACAUGGUGAAACCCCGUCUCUACUGAAAAUACACAAUUAGCCGGGCAUGGUGGAGGGUGCCUAUAAUCCCAGCUACUCUGGAGACUGAGUUGUGAGAAUCACUUGAACCCGGGAGGUGGAGGUUGCAGUGAGCCAAGAUCACGCCAUUGCACUCCAGCCUGGGCAAAAAGAGUGAAACUCCGUCUCAAAAAAAAAAAAAAAAAAAGAUUGCUACAUGCAUGGAGUGGGGAAAAUUGUGGUAGAAGAAAAGUAAACUUGGUUUGGAGAAUAAACAUUUAUUGAGCAUUUUCACUUGACCAGCUCUAAGGUGGGAAGAUUACAUAUAGUGUCUGUUUAAUAUUUAAUAUGUAUAGCCAUUAUUAUGUAUAUUGUAAACAUCUGUCAGAAGUUAUAAUUCCAAAAGUAAACUCUAAGCAACAGCUUUUUCAAAGUAUAUUUUUCAUGUAGCACAUUUCAUUAGCUCAUGAAAAGGUUAUUUCCCCAAAAUGUGUAAAAAUGUAAAGUGAACAAUGGCCAUUCAUCAGAAAUAGCAAGUGACAAUGAGCUCUCCAAGGAGCACUUCUUUUCAACACUCGACUUCUGGAGGCUGAAAUUCAAGUGGCCACAGAUGUCUUUAAUUCCAAAAACCUGGCCGUUCAGGCACAAAAGAAGAUCUUGGGUAAAAUGGUGUCCAAAUCCAUCGCCACCACCUUAAUAGACGACACAAGUAGUGAGGUGCUGGAUGAGCUCUACAGAGUGACCAGGGAGUACACCCAAAACAAGAAGGAGGCAGAGAAGAUCAUCAAGAACCUCAUCAAGACAGUCAUCAAGCUGGCCAUUCUUUAUAGGAAUAAUCAGUUUAAUCAAGAUGAGCUAGCAUUGAUGGAGAAAUUUAAGAAGAAAGUUCAUCAGCUUGCUAUGACCGUGGUCAGUUUCCAUCAGGUGGAUUAUACCUUUGACCGGAAUGUGUUAUCCAGGCUGUUAAAUGAAUGCAGAGAGAUGCUGCACCAAAUCAUUCAGCGCCACCUCACUGCCAAGUCACAUGGACGGGUUAAUAAUGUGUUUGAUCAUUUUUCAGAUUGUGAAUUUUUGGCUGCCUUGUAUAAUCCUUUUGGGAAUUUUAAACCCCACUUACAAAAACUAUGUGAUGGUAUCAACAAAAUGUUGGAUGAAGAGAACAUAUGAGCACAUGAGUUAAGAUUGUGACUGAUCAUGAUUUAUUUGAAGAUGGAGCACUGCUGAUUUAUGAAGGAAAAAAGAAGAAUUUUCUAAAGAUUACACAUAUUUCAGAAAGACUUUACCCAAUUCAGUUGUCAGACAUAAUGAUUUAUUUGAAGGCUUGUUUUAUUUGAAGAAAAGCAUAUUGCCAAAAAUUCUGGUUAAAAGCUUCCUAACGGGUAACAGACCAUGGGAGAGAUAUGUGGUUGGGUAAUGCAAAUGUAGUUAUACAAAGAAAAAUACAGAUGUCUCCAGACCUGAGGACUUUUUAAUAGGGCAGUUGUUGUGUUGGUGGCACAUUGGAUAUUUCUAACAUGUACAAAGCUAUGUAUUUUGAUUUACUUUCAUUUCUUGCUAUGUAUAUGUACUUUUCUUAAAAUGCCAAGAACUUUCUCUUGCUAUCAUUGCUCCUUUUGAAACAAUUCAAUUUUCAUGUCUACAGCUGACUGUUUUGUUAAGAUUGAGUCAUCGACAUUCAGGAUUUAAGUCUGAGGUAGUCAACCCUCAGGAAAAAAAAAAUGGCUUAUCUGAAAUCAGUACUGUGGAAAUGAACUAUAUUAGCUAUUAUGAAUAAUGUCCAGUAUAAGAAUAUGCUUCUGGAAUUGAGUUCUCCUUUUAAGUACCAAUGAUACUUAAAUUUCUCAGAAAUGUAAUGGUGUGUCAUUGCCUUGAAAUGCUUGCUUAGGGCUUCUUUUAUGUUAUCUUAAAAAGUGCUGGUGAAUUUUCCAUUUUUUACAUCCAUUUCACAUGUAAGAGACAAAAAAGUCUAGAUUGGUCUUGAUAUUGAGAUAAUAAAAAGUAAGUAGCAUUAAGAAAGGUAACAAUCUUCAUUCUACAGAUGAACUCAUUGAAACAAUUUAGGGGAAUGAGGGGCAAAAGGGGAGAAAUACUGCUAAAGAACAUGAGCAUAAAAAUGCGUGCGUUUCAGUGUUUAAGAAGGCUUGAUAAAGAAUGUCACUUUUUUAUUUAACUGAUAAGAUUUUUGUUAUUUUUUACUUUGAUAAGUAAACCAAAGAAUAUUUGUAUUUCAAGCAGUUUGUGUGGUGUUUCUAUAUAAUUUUCUGUGUAUAAAUAAUAAAGUAGGCAUUUGUUUAUUUUGUAAAAAAGAAAUGAAAAUCUGCUGGCCAGCUAUGUCCUCUAGGAAAUGACAGACCCAACCACCAGCAAUAAACAUUUCCAUUGUCACUGUGUCUAUGAUUUUUUUUUUUUUUUUUUUGAGUCUCGCUCUGUUGUUUAGGCUAGAAUGCAGUGGCAUGAUUUUGGCUCACUGCAACCUCUGCCUCCCAGGUUCAAGUGAUUCUCCUGCCUCUGCCUCCCAAGUAGCUGGGAUUACAGGCAUGCACCACCACACCCAGCUAAUUUUUGUAUUUUUAGUCGAGAUGGGGUUUCACCAUGUUGCCCAGGCUGGUCUUGAACUCCUGACUUCAAAUGAUCUGCCUGCCUCGGCCUCCGAAAGUGUUGGGAUUACAGGUGUGAGCCACUGUGCCUAUGAUUUAGUGUACUCUCUUGCCUUAAAUUUGCCUGCCUCCCAGAAUAUUGACAUUAAAAUAAUAGUUUACCAGGAAAGGUUCCACAACUAAAAAUUCCAGAAGUUGAGAUCUGCUCUAACCCAUUUCAGCCUAGAGAGGGUGGUCAGUUUCUCUGACACCCUCAUUUGCUUGGCUAAGACAAGCAGCAAAGGUGUAGAGUUUCUUCCUGUUUGAUAUUAAAUCCUGACACUAAGAUUUGAACUGAAAGUAUCAUUCUCACUUCCUAGAGCCAGUAGGUGAUCAGUAUAUGCUGUAACAAUAACACAGUGACUACAGAAAUGACCCUUCUAGCUUCAUAACUUGCUAAGUGGCUUAUAAAUGGAAUUCAGCAGCCUUCCUUGACCAGCUGUUUUCCUCACAUGUGAAGGCUGAGAAUGUGAUGGGGGGUGUGAGCUACUGACUGGAUGUGUUCUGUUCUCCAGAUCUCAAACAGCAGAGGUAUGGGAAACGAAAGCCCUGGGCAGUCCAUGGAUGCUUCUUGCUCAUCUGUAGCUAUAGACAGGACCAACCAGAGAGAGAAAACGUACGGAGGGAGAAAUCUGGAUCUCUCUGGACACACUGGAUCAUAGGGUUGUGCCAGCAGGCUAGCAAUCAAAUGUGCAUGGGAUUGGGGGAGCAAUGCUUCAUCUCCCACAGAGGGAAGGCAGUGAGGAGUAGACCGAAGGAGGGAAUCCUGUUUGCUACCAUUUCUCAGCAUUUUCUGGAGGGGACCCAUCUCCUUACCAGUGCUGUGCCUGAAAAGCAUGUCUUGGAUCAGGUCCAAAGUCGUGAUUAGCAAGUUCAUUUCUAAUACAAUAGGACUCCCCUUGAGCAUUUAGGGUGGCAAGGAGCGUGGGAGCUGGGAAGAAUCCCCACGUGCUUAGGGUAGAUAAAUCUGAGCCGAGUUAAUACUAAUUUGGGGAUCCUAUGAACCUUUUUAUAAAAUAGUAUCUGUUCACGUUUUGAAAAAAAUUGUGUUGUAAUUGAUUUUAUUUUGUGCUGGUGGCUUCUCUGCAAAAAUUAUGAGUGGAUAUGAUAAGUGGAUGAUAAUACUAAUGGACAACUAACGCAGAGUAGUUUGUAUUAUGUGUCGGGCACAUUAACUCAUUUAAUUCUGCCACAAUCUUCACCAUCUUAUAGAUAAGGAAACUAGGGGAAUAGAAGUUAAGGAAUUUCCUGAGGUCACAUGUGCUCGAGGUGUCCCAGCCGGAAUAUGUAUAAAAUCUUAUUUUCACUUAAAGAUGAUAUGGCUAAAGGCAGUGCUAGGAACAUCUUUGGCUCAGAGAAGCGUGGGCAGUAUGCUGCUGAAAUGGUUCCUCAUAUAGUGACAUUUUAGGCAGUACCUAAGUCAGCACAGGUCUGGCCUGUUCUCUAAAGAUCUGUGUAGAUGUUGUACAAAGACAUUUUUCAAAGUUUUCAACAUGACUCCUACUUUGGGGGCAUCUUGUGGCUCAGUUUUCUGUCUCGUGGAACUUCACUUCUAGGUGCUCACAAUGACUUUUAACGUUGACUUCUGAGGUGCAGUGAGCUGCUCCCCCACAGCUGUCCCUAGCAGUGGUGGGUUCAGAGCAUGACAAGGCACUCAAUGUGCAUUCACCAAGAGAAGCAAGGAAGCAGCAGUUCAGUACUGUGCUCCCUAGAGUAGGCACGGCAUCAGUUUCAAACUUCAACAUUAUUUUCCAGAUUUGGAGGCUCAAAAUAUUUGAGCAAGUUAAGUUAAGAAAUAGCCUUUUUCUGAUUAUUAGGCCUUUCAUAUACAACUCAAAAUUAGUUUAAGAGUAAAGCAUGGGGUGGGUGCGGUGGCUUAUGCUUGUAAGCCCAGAACUUUGGGAGGCGGAGGUGGGAGGAUCACUUGAGGUGAGGAGUUCGAGACCAGCCUGGCCAACGUGGUGAAACCCCACUGCUACUAAAAAUACACAAGAUUAGCCAGAUGUGGUGGCAGGCACCUGUAAUCCCAGCUACUUGGGAGGCUAAGGCAGGAGAAUCGCUGGAACCUGGGAGGCAGAGGUUGCAGUGAGCUGAGAUUGUACCACUGCACUGCAGCCUGGGCAACAAGAACGAAACCCCGUCUCAAAAAAAAAAAAAAAAAAAAAAAGCAUGAGUUAAGAACUUUGAUCGUACAGAAAUAUUGCGUUUUAAACUCUUAUAUAAUAGUAUGCCAUUCACAAUUAUCUGGAAAGUUCUUUUUCUCCCACCAUGUGAAUACACACACACACACACACACACACACAAUUUUUAAGCCCCCAAAGGCUUAAAAUAGUACUUUUUGUGGUCUGUACCGGUCAGUUGGAUUUUUACUAAGAAUUUUAAUUUAUCCUUGAGAUACUUGAUGAGUGUAUAUAAGCAGUUGCAAUUUAGCAUACAAAACCUGACAAAUGGUAAAUAAAAGAAUAUGUUUAUCCAAAUGAUGAAAUAUUUGUAGUAAAAAGUGCUAUUCAAUUGCCAGGAAAUUAAAAUACUCCAGUAAAAUGAAUUAAAUUAGCAUGUUAAUAAGAGUGAUAAUAUUUAAAAGUUUUAGUCAAUCUUGCAUUUCCAUACUUGCAUUAUCUAAACUAGUUGAACUUUUCAGUGUUUUACUUGAUAUAUUGCAUUCUUGAGCAUUAGGCUUCUAGGUGAUUUGUUAAACUCAUAGCAGGUUUUAGUACACAGUGCUGUUUAUGACAGAAAAAAUUUUAUCCUACCUCUGAAAUAAUUGUACUUUCUGUGAUUCAGAUAAAAACUUUAUAGAAACUCCCUAAUGAAAAUAUUGAAGCAUUAACCAGAAAAUGAGUCAGCUUUUUGUUUCCAAAAUGAUGCAACAGGAAAACCUUUAACUACUUAUAAUCCCGUAUAGUCACCAUCACCACGAAGUAUUGAAAAUCUGUUUUCUCUUUUACUAAGUGUCUGCACGGUCACUUAUGUAUACCCAAAGCCAGAAAGAUAUUUUUAUCUCAGGGAAAUUCCAGAAAUGGAAACAUUUUUGUGUAAUAUUGAUUCAUUUCUGUCUCACCAAAGAUGUGUUUUCCACGUAGCAAAGAACAUCAGCCCCACGUUAUAGGGAACAAGCGAGUCCCAAAUCGUACCAUCUGCUGAGCACUGAGAAAGGAUAUGGACAAGUCAGUCAGCAUUCACAAUUAAGAGAAAAACAUCUGUGCUUUGGAAAAUGUUCUUCAAGGAUAGAGAAUUGUGCCCUAUGUCCACCAAAUUUGCAUGAGAUCUUUAUAAGAUUAGACAGCCAGUGGAUAAGGCCCCUUAUCUUUCUUCAUGGAUGGCUGAGGAAAUUCUCCGCCUUCCCUGACAUCAGCUGCAUAACUGUAUUUCUGCCUCGUGGAAAUAAAGUAGAUGAUCAGGCACUUGCGGUUUGUUCUUAAUACAAGAAAGACAAUUUGAUUUUUAAAAGUUUUGAUUUGUAGAAUAAUGUAAGACAAUAUGUUUCUUUCUACUUUGGUUUUUCCAUUCAAAAGCUUACAGAUGAAUUCAUUCGUUUAAAACUGCCAGGCUGAGUGCGGUGGCUCAUGCCUGUAAUCCCAACACUUCGGGAGACUGAGGUGGGCGGAUCACCUGAGGUCCAGAGUUCAAGACCAGCCUGACCAACAUGGUGAAACCCCAUCUCUACUAAAAAUACAAAAUUAGCCGGGUGCAGUGCCACAUGCCUGUAAUCCCAGCUACUUGGGAGGCUGAGGCAGGAGAACCACUUGAACCCAGGAGGCAGAGGUUGCAGUGAGCCAAGAUUACACCACUGCACUCCAGCCUGGGCAACAAGAGUGAGACUUUGUCUCAAAAAAAAAAAAAGAAACUCUGUCUCGAAGUAAAUAAAUAAAUUUUUAAAAACCAACCUGAUGUGAAGUUGAAACACAAGACGCGGAAAUAAAAACUCAGAGUAUAAAUAUCUAUAUUGUUACCAUUAUCUGGGAUAAUUGAUGAUUUAUAAGAAGCUGAGGUUUCGUCUUCCUAGAAAUGGACUUUUAUUAGGCCAGCAAGAAUGACCACUUAGCCAUUUAAAUGAUUUGUCAGCAUCUUUUGCUGCUCUCUUCUAAGACCAUUGGUUUUCACUAAAGGAUAAAUACCUGCUAAGCAAAUUAUAAAAUACUAUAAGACAUUUAAUCUCCUGGAAGAGGACUUGCUGAUAAUUGGAUCAAAGUUCCAGCAUUAUUGCUCUUUUCGAAUCAUAUGGACUUAGUGUUCUCAUGACCGAGGAGUCACAUUUUUAGCUUGCUAAAAUAUUCACUGGAGAACAUGGUGAAAUCCACGAGUGGAAACGUUCCAUGGUAUUUUCAAACGCCACGUGUCAGGAAUUUGGCAUGCCUUCCUCUGGGAGAGGCACUGGAGUGUGGCCAGAUGGAACCCAGCAGGGUACAGAGGGCAUUUGUGGGAGCAGUUAGGAAACCAGGACGUCCAGCUUCUGCCUGCCAGGGAGCUCGCUCAUGUUGUCUCUGAAAUUUGCAUAAGAGCAAUUACCUCAUAUUCUAAUUUUAAAGAUACAAUUUUUAAAGACAUGGAAGGCUCUGAGACCUCCUGAAGGCUAUUCCUAUGUGAGGUAUUGUUUACGGGUGGCCUUUCACUAUUUCCAAAUCAGCGAUGAAAAGAAGACUGAGUCUAAAAUAAAUGAAGCAACAGACUUCAGCAGCCUGAGAGAAUUUUGUUCAAUUCCAGUCUCCUUAAAAAAAAAUCGGUUUUUGCUUUCAAUUUAGGAAAAUUGUUUUGGGUUGCAUUGUUGAAAGUAAUGAUUUCUAGCAGCUACUUAUGUAUAAUCUCUUAACCAAUUAAAUUCUGAAUCUCUUAAAUCA